GCGGCCGCAGGAGGAGCAGGAAGGGGCGGCGGGGCGCAGUGGGCGCCUGGUGGCAGCGCCGCCCCCAGCUCCCUGCCGGGCCGGCGCGCCCCUGAUUUUCUCGUAAGGACGGGCUGAAAGAGGAGGGGAGACAGAAGGAGACACUCCGGCCCGAGGACCACCACUGCCACUAGUAACGCCCCCUACACACUCUAGAAGUGCUCAGGCGAAUGACGAAGCGGCUGGUGACAAAGGCGGCGGCGAGUGCAGCGCGUGCACAGCCCGCGGAGCCGCGCGACCGCAAAUAUGACAAGCAUUUGAGCUAUUUGGCAACGUGGGGCCGGUCAGCGGGGCGGGCAGGGUCCCCGCGGGGGGCGAGGGGCAGAGAGCUGGCCCGGGCGCCCGUCUCGCUGCCUGCAGGGGUUCCUGGGCGGGGGUCCGCUGCGGGACACUCCUCCGAGGCCCGCACUGGUCCGAACGGCAGGAUGGGGGCUCCAGCCGUGAGCCGGGGACAGAAAAAGUCCCUUGCCCGCGUGGCCUCAGCCCGACACGAGAAGUGGGUCACCAAGUCCACGGCACUUUGGGAGCCGGACCGAACGAGUUGCAUCCUUCGGGGCCGGCCGGGGCUCGGUGCAGACCCGGCAGGAGGGAAGCCAAGCUAGGAGACGCAGCCAGGUCGGAGGCGCAGUCCUCUGCCCACAAGUUUCACAUUGAUAGCCUUUCCCUCCCGUGGAGUAAGCUUAUGCUUGGAACUACUUAAAUUUACCAGGGAAAUUUAUACUAGUUGGAAGAGAAUGUGUGUAUGCCCAAAUGGUGAGAAUUUAAGAGCACUAGGGAAAGAGGCCAGAUAGAUGGUUCCACUGGAAAAUUAAUGAUUAUUUUAAAAAUUACACGUGCAUUCAGCGUCAAGAUGUAAAAGGCAAUGCAGGCAGGCACCUUAAAAUUUUGGCUGCCACCCCAAUCAAUAUCAUUUCAGAUCACUUUGGAGUUUAAUGGUCCACUAUACUAGUUGUAUUUAAGAAUAAUAAAGCUUUAAGACCUAACAUAAAGGCGAUUGUAAGUCGUUAACAUCAAGAGAAAUUUAGACUUGUUUAAACUGUUCUGUAAUGAUUUGUUAUCAAUCAAAUUGAUGAUCUCAUCGAAAUUAAACUUGUGCUGAAAUGUUGAUAGAGGA